ACUUGGAGAAUUUUGCAAGGAGGGGCAAUAGUUGGAAUAAUUUUGGGUUUUAUUGUGUUGUAAAGAGGUUUUGUGAACUCCAAAGUGUUUUAAACCACUUUUAUUAUUAUUAUCAUUAAAGGAUGACAAUAAUGGUAUGCUACAGGGGACAUGGAAAGGAAAGCCAGUAGGUAAAGUGGUUUUUAGCUUUAGUUAGGUGGGUGUUGAAAGUGACUGAGUGUAUGAAUUUUUAAAAAGUGAUUUUGGGAUGGAUUACACUUGCUACCUUUUGUCAACUGAUUUUUAAAAACUUUCUGAAUUGUAGGAGAUUAGAAUUAAAGGGAUCAUUUUGAAGUGAUAACUAGAAAAUAACUGUGGUACCAUGGAGAAAACUAAAUUAAUAACUGCCCACUCUGGCUACCAAUCAGGCUAUUAGCCUGUAAAGCAAAAGUUUGAUGGGAAAUUAUUUUUUAACUCUCCCUUGGUUAGCUGACUUUUCUUUAGAAUUGUAUUUCUAAAUUUCCUUUCUACUUUUUAAAUUGGUAGAAGGGACAAAUGAGAAUACCUGAGUAAAGGCCCUAUUUACAGAGCACAAAUUGAGUUAAUUUGAUUAGCUUACUAGUACUCUUUAAAAUACUUUUUAUUAUUUGAGUAAUAAAUAUUCCAAGAAGAAAAAUUUAGAGAUACAGAUAAGCAAAAAUGAAGAAAAUAAAAAUAACCAUAUAAUCUUUUAGACUUUUUAAUAUCCAUACAUGCAUAUACAAAUUUUGAUAUUUAAUGAGAAAAACAUCAAAGCCACUUGACCAAAAAGCACCCUUUUAAAUUCGAGGAGAAAAGGCAGCAAAAGAUAACAUUUGUGAGCAUAUAUCAAUUUCCAAGUUCCAAUAAAUACCUCCCUCAAAAACAAGAUUAAAAAAAAGUUUAAAUUCACUUAUUAUUCAUUUAUUCAUUAACUACUUUUUUCAGCAUCCUGCUCUGUGCCAGGCACUGUAUAAGGCAGUGGGCAAGGUAAACCCUGCCAGAAAAGCAAACAGGGCUUUUGGCAUAGCGCCAAUUUUGUGCUUGGAAGAAGUCCAGUGAGGCUGUGAUAGUUUCUAGAAGCAAAAAAUUCAGUAGUGCCGUAGAGUGUGUGUGUGUGUGUGUGUGUGUGUGUGUGUGUGUGUGUGUGUGUUUCAGGGUAGUAGGAUGUUUUUGGAAAAGUGGUAGAGGCUACAGAAAUAAGCAAUGACUAAUUCUUGAAAGCCAGCCUAAGAAUUAUGAAUUCAUCCUGAGGCCAGUGGGGCCCACUCUUAAGAUUGGGCAGCGACUUGAUCCGAGUUUGUUUUCUACCAACUUGAGAACAGGAAACAAUCUGAAAUACUCGUUUCAUUUUACCCAGGUGUAAUAAAACACAGAAGGAUUGAUAAAUACGUUUUGUCAUUUUUAAGAGGAUAAGCUUAAUCUCAGAGGAGAGCAAAUGCACAUAUAGAAAUGAUAAAGUAUGGUUAUCGAUGUUCUAUUUUAUCUAAUAUUUUAUGGUAAAAUUUAUAUUUUGCUCUGUCAAUAGGGAAGUUUAUAAAAUGUUGUGAGUUAUCAUUUGUAAAGCAUGAAUUCUUUAUUAAAAUUAUCUUAUUAUUUAAAAAUAUACAGUCAGUCCUCUCUGUGGGUUCUACAUCCGAGGAUUCAACCAAUAGUGGAUUAAAAAUAUUCGAAAAUCAAAAAUGGAUGGUUGCAUAUUCACUGAUCAGUGUAGAUUUUUCUUCUUGUCAUUAAUCUCUAAACAAUACAGUAUAAGAACUGUUUACAUAGCAUUUAUAUUAGGUGUUGUAAGUAAUCUAGAGAUGAUUUAAAGUAUAGGGAAGGAUGUACAUAGGUUAUAUGCAAAUGCUACACCAUUUUAUGUAAGGGACUUGAGCAUCCAUUGAUUUUGGUAUCUGCAGUGGGUGGGGGGUGACCCUGGAACAAAUCCCCCAUGGAUGUGGAAGGAUGACUGUAUUUAAAUUUAAAAUUUAAGUAAUAAAAAAGUCCUAUGUUAUAUAUUACUAAUAGUGUAUUUCUACGUAAAUCUCAUGAUUGUCUUAUCAGAGCUUUGAAAUGCAACUGAUAGUAUUUAGGGCUAUUUAUUUUUUGUUGUAGUUAUCAAAGAUACAAUAAAUUAGGUUUAUCUCUAUAUAUUUAAUAUAAUUUGCAACAUCCAGCAUGAGAGGAAUUAACUAAAGUUUGCAGCCAUUGCUGUUCUAAGCAAAAUUCUUAAGUGCUUUGAUCAUUAAUUUAGCAUGCUUAAUAUUCAUUUAAAAUCGGCAGUGAGGAGCAUAUGCAGGUCAACUUGAUUUUUCUUUUCUCUUUUUUUUUUUUUUUUUUUUUUGAGAUGGAGUCUUGCUCUGUCUCCCAGGCUGGAGUGCAGUGGCACGAUCUCGGCUCACUGCAAGCUCCUCCUCCCGGGUUCACACCAUUAUCCUGCCUCAGCCUCCUGAGUAGCUGGGACUACAGGUGCCCACCUCCACGCCCGGCUAGUUUUUUGUGUUUUUAGUAGAGACAGAGUUUCACCGUGUUAGCCAGGAUGGUCUUGAUCUCCUGACCUCAUGAUCUGCCCGCCUCGGCCUCCCAAAGUGAUGGCAUUACAGGCGUGAGCCACCGCGCCCGGCCAACUUGAUUUUUCUUUCGGGAACUGGAAUAAAGUGACAUUAUUUGAAAAAUCUUCAAUAAAGGUAAUGAUUUUGAUAUCAAUUGUAAGUUAGCUAGUUAUUGGUAGGAGAGACAAUGAUUGCACUGGCUUCCAUUUUCCUUUGCUGGUUGAUUAUCUAUAUGGUGUGUACUGGGAUUUGUUUAUGUUAUGGAUAUAUACUUCUUGUCUGUUUUGCUUGUCUUCUGACAAGUCUAGGAGCUUUGAAAUGUUUAAGAAUUGUGUAUGUGUUGUAGUGGCCUGGUGUCAUUUAGAAUAUACCUGAGAAAUUGUGUCAAACUGCAAACUAAAACCAAAGUGAAAAAUAGUUUUGCCAGCCCUUUAAGAUAUUAAAGAUUGCUUAGAGAUACUUUGUUAAUGUUAUUCAUUUUACUUAUCACAUUUUUUUCUUAGUAUGGAAGGUUUUUUUGUUAGUAUGUAAGUAAUACAACAAAUUAAGCAAUGGAGUUUUUAUCUGUGUAUUUAAGGAAUUAUAAAAGGCAAAGAAACAAGUAUAGGUUAAUGUCACUUUUCCAUAUCUACCAAUUCACUUAAGUAGCUUUAACCCAAAUAAAACAAAGGGUCUUGACUCUUGAUUCUGAUCAGAAAAUGUCAUCCUUUUGUCCAUUUACUUUAAAUAAGUAGUUAUUUGUGGUACAACUUGCAUAUUUCUGAUUGUUUCUGUAGUUACCUUUGAUUUUUUUCAUAUAAUUGCAAGGCUGAUGAUACUUUGAAAAUUUUUGGACUUCCUUACCUUUGACAGAGAAGAGAAUAGUUUUGUAUCUUUAAAUGCAUGGACAUUUAACUAUUUGAAAUAAGUUCUAUUUAGUAUUCAGAGCCCUAUUCAGACAAAACUAGGGACUGUAGCUGAGGCUUAUGGGAAGCUUUCAAUUUCCUAAGUUAUAUUGCUACAGCCACUGUACUGAGAAAGAACUACAGUACUGUCUAACUAUGGCAUUUGGUCAGAUCAAGGUGAGUUAUAUAGAAAGGAAAAGGGAAUCAAUAAAAUAUAGGAUUAAUAAUUUUUUAGAUUUUGUAACAGAUACGAUUUGUCAACAAAGUUGGAGGAUUAAAGACAACAAUUCCUGGGGCUGUUUGAUUUUAAGUAAUCCAAUCUGGAUAGAUUAUAAUAAAUUCACGUUUUUUGAAAUAUAUAGUUUACUAGUGAGACUAUUUCAGUGUUAAGACCAAUGAGUUUCCGUCUGUGUGGCUAUAAUGGGGGUUUCUGACCUUUUUUUUUUCUAGCUGUUGAUGUAUUGAUGGGAAUCCCUACAACCAUAAUUUACCAUGACUAAGACAUUCAUUUUUCUGUUGUUUGAAAGUUAGAGAGAUAAGUAUCUCUCUUUUCCCUCUAUAUUUGUUUAUUACUGUAUGAUUAGUUCUCUUCUAUUAGUCAAUAUAACUGAUUUCCAAGGUAUAUUUUCCAUUUAGUGGAAUCCUGAGAUUGUUGGAGCCUUCAUAUUUUUUUCCUUCAGUCAUCUUGCCGAUUGACACUAAAAUGAGCUUAAUAAGAUUUUUAUCUAUUAUUGGAGGAUUCCAGGCCUAUUUAUUUUCCCUAGGAAGGCUAUAAUAUUUAACAAACAAGUUUAUUGAAAUAUUUUAGAACUUUAAAUCUUUUGAAGUUACCCAAAUUGGAGGGUCUUACAACUUUGAAUUACUUUCUAAGACCUCUUUCCUUCCAGUAAUGAGAAACAUUUAUUCAACUUUUUAAAAGACAGAAAUCAUCUUUUUAAAAUGUACUGUUUUCUAAUUGUCUGAAAUGACAAGAGAUCACUUACCCAGCAGUGCACAAGACUUCCAAAAUAGCUGAGCAGCGGGUGAGGGGCUAGAAGGCGGGGGGUGGUGGUGGUAUCUUUUUUUAAAAAAGUAUGUUUACUAGAAAGGGUAUAAGAUACUUUGCUUUUGUUAUAGGUGCACUUGCACAAAACUCAUUUUAACCUGUAGUCACAAUUUCUUCUGUAUGACCCACCCAAAGUAACCAGGCUGCAAAGCAUUAUACCACAUAUAAAAGCAACAUUCAGAUUGCUUGUUUUGCUUUUAUUUAUUUGCAUAUGUAAUUUAUUGUGCCUGUGAAAAAAGGAAGUUCUUAUAAAGAGCAACAAAAUAGGAAAAACAAGCAAAUUGUCAUUUCUUCUGGUAGAUUAUGAUUUAGAAUUUAGGUAAAAAAAUUAAGUUUGAGUGAUUCCAUUUAAUCUUGGUAGAGUUGUGAUAGCUUAUAUGUAAAAGCAAAAUCAUUUUAUUUAAAACAUUAUGAAAAGAUGCUGACAGUAAAUUUACGGAGUGCAUUAGUGUUACUAUUGGAUGUGUUGGAAUCCAGACUGUAAAUUAUUGUUACUCUGUUACAUAAAGACUACUAAUUUUUAGUACAUGUUUAUAUUGAUUUAUUCAUAUUAUAGAUCAUGGAAUACCACUUCAUUUUGAAAAAAGAGAAUUAUAGUUUUCAUAUUUAGAAACUGAGAAAGGAUUUUUUAAAAAUGAAGAAACAGAUGGUUUAACAUCAUAUGCUCUUAAUUUUUGCAUAUUUUAGUUUCUGAAAUAAAUGUAAUUAUGGUUUUGAUUAUGUUUUCCUACUUUUAAUGUAGCAUUUCUAGGAUUACUAUUAAGACCUUCUAAUUAACAUAGGUGGAUGAUAUUAGAGGUAACCUCGAUUUGAUAUAAGACAGCAAAUCACAGACCAUCUUUUGAAGCCCAUUUUAAGGCCUUGAAAUCCAGUGCCUCAAUGCACUGCAGUGAUGAAGCAGCAGAAGUUUUUGUUCUCCUGACAUAAUUGAAAUGAAUAUAAAACUUUUCAUUUCUCUGUUUAAGUUAAUAUUAUUAUAUCAAUUAUAUUAUUGUAAUAUAAUUUAUUAUAACAAUAUUAUAAUAAAAGACAAUUCUGUUUGGGGUUUAUCUUAUCACCAUCAUAUCUUACAUAAGCAAUAGAGGAGAGAAGCAAAAUUUUGGGUAUGAGUCUUCCCAAGUUAUCUACAAGUUAAUGGUUUAUUGUUCUUAAGGGAAAGGAAAGAAUAUCUUUUAACAUGGAUGAUAAUCUCUUCUAUAGAUGUGUUGAAACCUGGAAAUUGAAGAAAAUCCUAUUAAUUGAACUUUAUUUGGGUAAGGUAAUCGACUUUGUAUUGUUUAGGGUCCUUUACUGAAAUGGCUACUGGAACACUUGAAGUAGGUAAACAUUUUUGCCUGAAGCUUAUUAAGGCCGCCAGGAAAUCUUUUCUCUUACUUGGCAUAAGUAAAGAUAUUUUUCCAUAGGAUAUUGCCCAGGAUUCAUUUGGCUUGGCAGUUGCAUGGAUUGUUUUGUGAUUGCUUUUUGAGGGCAAUAAUUCUGCCCCAUGAAAAUAUUAGUCAUUAUUAUUACUAUUUUUUUAUCUUUGGUCUUCUAAAAAAGAUAAAGGGCCGAUGUAUAAUUUCUUAGUAAACUGUUAACAUAUUUGAAUGACCCAAGGAACAUAAUGAUGUUCUGCUAAUGACAUCAUUCUCAUCUUUCUGUCCCAAUGAGAUAGAUAUUGUACUCUAUUUUGUGGACAAAGAAUCUGAGGCAAAAGCAGUUAGAAACUUAAGGGCACGCAUUUCAGUAUUUAUAGAAUCUACAUUGGAACCCACUUGUUUUCAUUGAAGUUUAAUCGUAUAGAGUUUCAGUUUUGCAGGAUGGAAAAGUUCUGGAGAUCUGUUUCACAACAAUGUGAAUAUACUUAACACUGCUGAACUGUGCACUUAAAAAUGGUUAAGAUUGUAAAUUUUCUGUGUGCACAAUAAAAAUAUAUUAGAAAUUAUUUUCUUUUCAUUUGCUUAUUAAGUACGUUUUUAGUGAAGAAUAUUCUGGAGGUAAAAUGUUCAUCAUUUGGCUCAUCUCUCAUCCAAUAUGAAACUGCUUCAAUUUCAUCACUUAAAAGGAACCUGAGUUUCUACUUUAGUUUGGACUGAGCUGUAAAAAGUCUUUUCUUUCCUUUCUACCAGAUUGUAUUUCUUUUUAAAAUCUAGUCAAUGGAAAAUUAAAAGAUAAGAUAUAAAUCAGAAUUAUGACCUAUAAUUUAUAUUAUGACUUAUAUUAUACCAAGAACAAAUGUAUUUGAGAAUCUCCUGCCUUUUUCGCUGAAGCUCAAGUAAAACUGUAGAUUUUUAGAUUUUUAGAUGUUUUUGACUAUGUAAACAUUUCAAGACCAGGUGUGGUGGCUCAGGCCUGCAAUAGCAGCACUUUGGGAGGCCGAGGCAGGUGGAUCACCUGAGGUCAGGAGCUCGAGACCAGCCUGGCCAACAUGGUGAAACUCUGCCUUUAUUAAAGUUAUAAAAAUUAGCCAGGCGUGGUAGCGGGCGCCUGUAAUCCCAGCUACUUGGGAGGCUGAGGCAGGAGGAUUGCUUGAACCCAGGAGGUGGAGGUUGCAGUGAGCCGAGAUCGUGCCACUGCACUCCAGCCUGGGCGACAGAGCGAAAUUCCAUCUCAAAAAAAAAAUUCUUUUAAAAGUACACUUACUCUGUAAUUUUGGUAAUGAUGAAGCGUUCAUUUUAAAAAUAGAGUAAAAAGUACUUGUGAUUUAUUUUCAUGAAACAGGAUAGAAAUCCCUCAUCUCAUUUAAUUAAAAAAGAAAUAACCACUGGUAAAAUCUGAUCUUUUCCUUUCUCCAAUACCUGUCAAGAUUUACUUUGUAUAUCUGUAUUUUCUAAAAUUGUUACCCUAUAUCUUUUACAUUAAAAAUAGAUUAAUAAUUAAGGGUCAAUCCUUUAGAAUAGGUAUUUUAAAUUAUGUGAUUUAGUCUAUCUAGUGUAUUUGCCUAUUUAUAUAACUAUUUAUUUUGACCUAUCUAUAUAACCACUUAUUUCUCAGUCAACCCUCUGUAAGUGUAGAUGUCUAAGUCUAGCUUAUAUAUAACUUACAAGUUAUAUGAAAAUACCACAUUGUAUCUCAUAAAUGUAUACAAUUACUUUUCAAUCAAGAAUAUUAAAAAUAAAUAUAAUUAAAGGUUAAAAAAGCAAAAAUAUGCUGUCCUAGAUUUCUCAGUGCUUUUAAAGUAUGAAACAUGUUCAUUUUAUGAAUCACAACCUAAUACUCAUAGUGUUAAAUACUAUGAGAGUAAGCCUUUAAGUAUAGAGUAUUGAGUUAAUACUCCUCAGUUCAUGGCAUGGUAUUAUCAUUGGUUCAUGUCAGGCCUUUCUGCUGUUUAAUUGACAUUCAUUCAUUUACUCAUUCAUUUAUUCUCUAUACCUGUUCCUCAUUUCUACAACCCCCAGCCCCAUAGGAAAUCAUUUAGACCUACCCAUUUUGCUGUGUGUAUAUCCAGUUCCUAUUUCUAAUUGCUGCAAAGGGGAUUUACUGUUUCACAUUGUUUUAUAAUUGCUUGAAAAUUCCUAUCUUCACGUUAUUUCUUUAUAUUUUUUUAAAGAGAGAAGCCAACCUAUUUGAAGGUAGGCUAGUUCAGAUGAACUUUUUAUGCGCAAAUAUAACCUAAUUCAGUGAUUCAUAAAAAUGAGUAAGUUUAACACUUUGAAAGUAUUGAGAAAUUGAGGACAGCAUAUUUAUUUUUUAACCCAUUAACAUUAUAAUUUUUAUUUUUAAUAUUUUUGAUUGAAAAAUAAUUAUAUACAUUUAUGUGGUACAAUACGGUGUUUUGAUAUAUGUAUGCAGUGUGGAAUGAUUAAAUCAGGCUAAUUAACAUAUCACCUCUCUUACCUAUCAUUUUUUAUGGUGAGACAUUUGAAAGGUAUUCUCUUAAUUUUAAAAUACAGAAUACUGACUUUUAAGACUCAAUAAGUAAUUUAAAAAUUAAACUUCAUUCUCUAUUAAACAUCAAAUUUAGUUUUUCUUUGUUACUGGUUAUAGCAUUGCAUAGGGCCUCAGUUUUAGUAGGGAUUCAGUAGAUGCGUUGGUUUCAUUUAAUGCCAUACCCACUAAUUUGUUAAUUGGCUUGGACAUUUGCGCAAGUUAAUUCAUGCUUGGAGCUUUAAUAUUUUAAAAUGAUUCAGACAUCAAUCAAGCAACCAGAAUUUAUUACAAAAUCUGUAAGAUAUAUAGUUUCUAGUUUACAUUCUCGAUGUUGACAGCUUUCCUCGCCCAAAUUAUUGCAUCUGAUCCACACUAUUAUUGUGUGUGGUAAGCAUGUCAGGCAUUAUAUCCAUUUUAGUAAAGGAGAAGUUGAGUCAAGGCAUUAAGUGGCUUGCACAAGGUUAUAUGGCUGUUAAGUCAUAGUCAGGACUAUAACUGAAAUUUUCUGACUCCUCGACCAAUGUUCUCUAUACCAAUGUUUUCAAACUCUGUUAUAGAAGGAACUGAAGGAGGUGACAUAAUAUGAAAUGAGGACAAGAGAGGCCAUCUUAGAUGAAAUGUUUUAUUUAUUUAAAAAAAGAUGCUGCCCUUUUAAGUAAAACUUUGAAAAUCAUUGCACUGUAUUGUCGCCGUUUUUGUUUUGAAAUGGAAGUGCUAAGUCAGAUUUGUCAAUGGUAACUCCAAAAAGGGAUAAGAAAAAGUCAUCUGUUCCUGAAAUGCUUGUUGCAUUUACAUUAUCUAUCUUGUCAUGUCACUCCCCAUUACCUUUAGAAUAAAACUUAGACUAACGGUGGUUCACAGGACGCUGAAUUAUCUGGUCCUUGCCUAAUUCUGCAGACACAUCUCUUGCUAUUUUCCCUUUUAUUCCUGAUCCCCCAUAGCCUUCUUUCAGUCCUUGAAUAUGCUAGCCCUGUGACACCUCAGGACAGUGUUCCCUUUCCCCAGCCCUUUCUAUGGCUGGCUUCUUUUGAUCUAUCAGGUUCCAGUGGCCUUCCCUGACCAUCCUUUCUAAAGUAGGUCCUCCCUUAUUCUCCACCCUGUACCUUGUUUCACUUGUAUCCUGUAACACAAAGUGAAAUUAGUUAAUUACUAGUAGACUCUAAACUCCAUGAGUGCAGGGACCAUGUUUACCAUGUUUUCUUUUGAAUCCUUAGUCACUUUGCCUAUAGUUGGCCCUGGUUAAAUAUUUAUUGAAUGAGCAAAUGUUGAAUGAAUUAUGAGUUAUCAAGAGAUGCUCAAUUUAUAUUUACUGUCCUCUGAGAAAAAUCUCAAAUUAUACGCAUUUGAUGAAUAUUUCCAUAAAAUGAUUUUAAUGCAUUAGUGCCUAAUAGUUGUAGUCAUGAUUUAAAGAAUGUUGCAUGAGAUUUUUUUUUUUGAGGUGGAGUUUUGCUCUUGUUGCUCAGGUUGGAGUGCAAUGGUGCGAUCUCAGCUCACUGCAACCUCUGCCUCCUGGGUUCAAGUGAUUCUCCUGCCUCAGCCUCCUGAGUAGCUGGGAUUACAGGCAUGUGCCACCACUCCCGGCUAACUUUGUAUUUUUAGUAGAGACAGGGUUUCUCCAUGUUGGUCAGGCUGGUCUCGAACUCCUGACCUCAGGUGAUCUGCCUGCCUCGGCCUCCCAAAGUGCUGGAAUUACAGGCGUGAGCCACUGCACCUGGCCCAUAUUCUUCAUAUGUGAUUAAUACCCCCAACAAUGUUGUGAAGUUAGUAGUAUAUUCUACUUUAUAGGCAAUGCAACAGACUUAGAAAGGUUUGUUGAUAUUUGCCCAAAGACACUUAGCUAGUAAGUGGCAGAACUGGGAUUUGAACUUAGGUCUGUUUGUAACUAAAGUCGGCACUAUUUUCACUCUAUUUUGCCGCUUCCUAAAUUAAUGCUUAGGUUCUCUGGAAAAUUUGCUUCUGAUGAACACUUUCCUUUCCCAAUGACGCUGGAUAAAUGGGGUGUUACUGUAAUAAGGUGCUAAUUGAAUGGCGUACAGAGUAAGUGCAAAAGAAAUUAAAGGAGGAAAAGGUAUGUGCUGAAGUCAUCAGGGAAACCUCAUGGAGCAGCUGUGGGACUUUAGUUCAUUCAAUUAAUGCUGUGAAAGUGUUCUGCAUACUGGACCGUGUAGGAUGAAUGGGAUAUAAAUAAAUAUAGAAGGGAAUUGAGGGUAUUUUAGUUUGGAGAAACUGCUUAGAAGUGUUGUGGGUAUCCUGGAAGCAGUAGGGAGGACUAGUGUGACUGGAAGAGAGGAUUUAUCUUGGAGAAAAGUGGGAUAUUUGUUGAAAAAGUAGAUGAGGAUGAUUGGGGGUAUAUAAACUAUAUAGAAUUUAAUUUUCUCUGUGGUUGCUAAGAGCAGUGUCAUUGUGGGAUACAAUAACAGUUUAGGAACUUCAGUUGGUAAUAGUAUGCAGGUUUUAAGUAUAAUAGUGCAGCAUUGGUAGCACAGUGAAUAACAGUGGCAGUUCUGGCCCUGGGCUUGAAUUCCACCCCUUUCACUUGCCGGUUUGUGAGCUUGGAAUAUUAUUUCACUUACUGUACUGUUGUUUCUCCUCUGAAAUGGAAAUUGAACAGUAGAACCUUUGGCCUGAUCCCAGAGAUUAUGAUUCAGUGUGUCUAAGGUAUGGGGCAGGAAUACCCCCUCCUCCCAAAUCAGAUUUAGUUACAUCUCCUAUGUGGUCCCGGAGGGCUCUGUAUUUGUUCAGUGUUUCUUUUCUGACCUCAGGUGCAAAAAGUUGAAUUCAUCAAACUCCUCAGAUUAAUGACAGACUAUCAGCUUUUGGCAAGACUCCUCUCUUGUUUUAUUUAAAAUAGUUCUCAUUUAUCCCCAGUAUUCAUUCUAAUUCUCUGCCUACAUAGAUGUUCGUACUAAUGUUUUUUUGAAUAUGUCUGUCUCUUUAAAAAAUAUAUGGUGCUGUUUUAUGCACACAUAUUUUUAAUUUAUAUAAAUUAUAUUGUGCUAAAGAUCUUCUGUUUCUUUUUUCAUUCAACAUGUUAAAAUGCCUUUUAUGAUAGAAAACUUCAAACAGAUCCAAAUGUAGAGAAAGUAUCAACCCACCAUGUGUCCAUCAUCCAGCAUCAACAAUUAUCAGCUCAGAGCUGAUCUUGCUUCAUAUUAUUAACCAUUCCUCCCCUAGUGCCUCCUCCCCACAACUCCACCUCUGCAAACUGUAUUAUUUUGAAGCAAAUCUGAGACUUUUUAAAACUGUAUUUCAGUGCCAAAAACAUCAAAAAACCGCUACCCAUUUGGAUCUCUGUAUAUCUGUUUCAUAACUUGUAACUGCUCUAGGUAUGUCAGUGAAUGCACUUACCACAUCUCUGGCCCUCUGGUGAUGGUCACCUAGUUUGUCUGUAAUAUUCUGCUACCACAGACAACUUUGAUUUUCAUUUUCAUACAUGUCCUCUUAUGGGCUUUUGGGAGAACUUUGAUUUUUCAGAGUGGGAUCUCUGGAUAAUAGGGUAUAUAUACAUAUACUUCAUUUCACUAAGUUUUGCCAACUUGAUUUCCAGAAUGUCUGUACUAGUGUACAUUCUCACUAGGAGUACAUAGUAGUUCUCUUUUCCUCCAUUUCCACUGGCACUCUGUAUUAACUUACAUUAUAUUUUUGCCAAUCUUUCAUUUGUAAAGUGGUAUAUUAUUUAAAUUUUUAUUUCUCUGAUUAUUAGUGAGGUUAGUUAUCUCUUCACGUAUUUGUUUUCUGUUCUCCUUAAGACCUCCCAUUCUUGCUGUUUUAUUAUGCCUAAAAAACUCUUUCCCCUUAUUCACGUGGCUCACUCACUCCAUUCAGAUCUCUUCUUAAAUGUCAUGUCCCCAGAGAGUUCUGCUUUAUCUUUCAUUGUCUUUAUCACAACAAAACCUUAUAUUAUGUUAUGUAUUUAUUUAUUUUCUCUGCUCAAGUUCCUUGAAGGCAGAGACCUUACCUGUGUUCACACCUGUAUCCCUAGCACUUAAAAAGAAUUCAUCUGUGCCUUAUUCCAGUUCACUCUUGUAAGGGUGAUGCUUGUGAUCCCCUCAGCCCUCAUGUAUUCAUUCGUAUUAUAUUGGAGGUUAGCACUCUACGUAUAUGAAUAUCUGCUCCAUGUAGGAGCUCAGAAAUCAGCUCAAACAUUUUUAUCAGAGAUAAGAUGGGAAAAAAACAUCACAUUGGGGGAACCACCAGGAUUCUUACAUUCUUGGUGGUGUGUAUUUUGGGAUCUCUACUGUGCAGCUCCAGAGAGACGUGAAACAUGUGAACACUCAAGUGAAGCAAAAGCCUUCCAUGAUUACAGUGCUGCAGCAGCUCCCAGUCCAGUGCUAGGAAACAUUCCCCCAGGAGAUGGCAUGCCAGUAGGUCCUGUACCACCAGGGUUCUUUCAGCCUUUUAUGUCACCUCGGUACCCUGGAGGUCCAAGGCCCCCAUUGAGGAUACCUAAUCAGGCACUUGGAGGUGUCCCAGGAAGUCAGCCAUUACUCCCCAGUGGAAUGGAUCCAACUCGACAACAAGGACAUCCAAAUAUGGGUGGGCCAAUGCAGAGAAUGACUCCUCCAAGAGGAAUGGUGCCCUUAGGACCACAGUCUGACCCUUGGUUAUCAUUACAGAACUAUGGAGGUGCAAUGAGACCCCCACUGAAUGCUUUAGGUGGCCCUGGAAUGCCUGGAAUGAACAUGGGUCCAGGUGGUGGUAGACCUUGGCCAAACCCAACAAAUGCCAAUUCAAUACCAUACUCCUCAGCAUCUCCUGGGAAUUAUGUAGGUCCUCCAGGAGGUGGAGGGCCACCAGGAACACCCAUCAUGCCUAGUCCAGCAGAUUCAACCAACUCUGGUGAUAACAUGUAUACUUUAAUGAAUGCAGUACCUCCUGGACCUAACAGACCUAAUUUUCCAAUGGGUCCUGGGUCAGAUGGUCCCAUGGGUGGAUUAGGAGGAAUGGAGUCACAUCACAUGAAUGGCUCUUUAGGCUCAGGAGAUAUGGACAGUAUUUCCAAGAAUUCUCCCAAUAAUAUGAGCCUGAGUAAUCAACCGGGCACUCCAAGGGAUGAUGGCGAAAUGGGGGGAAAUUUCUUAAAUCCUUUUCAGAGUGAGAGUUACUCCCCUAGCAUGACAAUGAGCGUGUGAUCCAUUACCAAGUCUCCUCAUGAAAACCACAGUGAGUCAGCCCUUCACAGAACUACUACGGAAGAAAAUUAUUCAUCACAGUGUACAGUUAAACAAAGGAAUCUCAGUCACACCAAACCAACCUUUUUAUUUCCUGCUCUCUCCCCUCUUUUGUGAAGAAAGCGGGUCCAAAUGUGAUUCAAACAACUGUACGGAGUGGCAUAUUAGAAUUGCCCUAAACUGAACUGCAAAUAAUUAUGUGUGUAUGUAUAUGUGUGGGAAAGAGAAUGUACUGUAUAUGUGUAUGUUAUACAGACAUAUACACAUACAUACAUUGACCCACAGGACAUUGUAAAAUAUUAUCACAUGACAUCUUAAGUAGAAAUAAGUAGGGACUUUUAUUCCAUCCUUUUUUUCACGUUUACAUUUUAAUUAUUACAAGUUGCUCCUGCCCCCUCCCUGAACUAUUUUGUGCUGUGUAUAUCACUGCUUUAUAUAAGUUAUUUUUUAAGGUGAACUCAGAUGUUAUGGUUUUGUAAAUGUCUGCAAUCAUGGAUAGGAAUAAAAUCGCUUAUUUGAGAGCUUUCAUUAAAUUGCGUCUGAUGCAAGUUAUCCUGUGAAUCACAAAGUGUACUGUCUCAAAAAAUAGAAGAAAAUGUGUCUUCGUCUUUAUGUUGAAUCAAACAAUUUCUCAGUUACCUUCAGUGAAAAGUAUUUUUUUAAUUUUUAUUUGAGAAAAACACUUCAAAUCAGUAAAAGCUUAACUGGGGCCUCACACAGUAUAUUUCUGCAAUAACUGCUUUAAACGGAGUUCUUGAUUUGUUUGUCUUAGAUGAUACAGAAAUCAUUAAAUAGCCCAAAUCAUUUAGACCAUAGCAAUAAAGUGACCGGGGUUGUCAUAUAUUUAGCAACAUCUUUUCUCUUUAACAUGAUGAAGCCCAAAAGUGAUAACAAAAGCAUUUGCUUGAAUUUGUCACUUCUCACCAGGAGUACUAGAGGUAAAUUUUUAAUAACAUACUAAUGUGAAAUGGUAUCUGGUUUUUAUUCAGACUUUUUGUGAGCAUAUUCUUAUAGACACUAGAAAUAAAUACAUAGAAGGAGACUUUGAGCACAAGGGAGAAGAGAGUUAUUAGCACUCCUGAGGCCUCUGGAAUGCUGCUUUUCUAUCCAGGUAUCUUGCUUGCUACCAGCAGAAUUGACUGGUAUUGGUUCUCACUGGCCAGGGAGCCUCUGCUCUGUUCCUGGAAUAUAAGGCUUUUAUUCAGGAGCAAAUCAUUGAUAGUAACUUUGCUUUAUCUAGCCAUUGACUUCAGCAGGCUAAAACUACAUUGUGUAACUGACUGUUCAAAAAAGAAUAAGUAAAUUUUUUUUAAUCUAAUUCCCUUAUGGAAAGCACCUUGCUCUAUGGCACUUUCCAGAUCUUUUGGGAUUUUGUGCUUAAUUAUACAUACAUACACCAAAAUCACAAUAGAAAGAUAUGAAGACUUUAAUUUUAGACUCUGAAAGAUAACUGGGUGAUCCUUUGUGUUAAAAUUGUGAUACAAACAACCAUUGAUAAAUACCAACUAUGAAUCCAAACUCUAGAGACUUUGAAAAGCAUUGUUUAAUUGCAGGUAAGAGGAAUCUUCUCUUUCCUUUAGGCUUAUAGUCUCUAAAGUGAAAAUUUGGCAGGAUAUAGUCAUGCAGCUCAUAAUGACAUUCCAAUCAACCACAGACUGCAUAUACAGCAGUGGUCCUAUAAGAUUAUAAUACCAUAUUUUUAGCAUAUCUUUUCUAUGCUUAGAUACACAAAUACCAUUGUAUUACAGUUGCCUUUGGUAUUCAGUACAGUAACAUGCUGUACAGGUUUGUAGCCUAGGAGCAAUAGUUUAUAUUAUAUAGCCUAGGUGUGUAGGAGCCUAUACCAUCUAGGUUUGUGUAAGUACACUCUAUGAUGUUCAGACAAGGACAAUAUUGCCUGACAAUGCAUUUCUCAGAAUGUAUACUUAUCAUUAAGUAACAUAUGACUGUAUGUACUAGUUCCUGAUGACUUACUUCUCUCAAAUUCAUAAUGAUUUAGUCCUUGUAAAAAUAAAGAUUUUGCCUGUGCCUAAACAGGGAUACUAGGCAGAACUGUUGAGAAAAAAAAGCUGAAUUAAAUUUAUGUUGCAGAUUUAAACUAUCAUAAAAUGAGCCUCAGUUAAUCACACACAGUAUUCAGGUGCCUAGGAGUGCACACCGGAGAACAGCCUCAUGCUGUCAAGCUGCAGAAACCUUUCAUGCAAAUUCAGAUGAAAAGGUCUUUACCUCAAGCCAGGGUAACCUGAAUGAAGGUGAUAGUUUGUCCAGACACCUGACUUUACCAAGAAGAAUUUUGACUUUCAUAUUUUAUGACAAUCAUAUAAAAAUUGACAGUCCUUUGAUUAUUAAGCUUAAUCUUAUAAUGCUAGAAUUUUCAAAUAUUUUGUUGACUCUUCUCCAUUGUUACCGAUCUUGAAAUUCUUUUCUUCGCCUUCUGAGAAGGUAUUAUUUCUUAUCACAAAGAAUGAUGAAUAUGAUUUUAUCUACCCUUAUUUUGGGGGUAAUACGAGAAUAUGAAUUGCAUCAUGAUCCCCAUUAUUUCUAACCUAAAAGUAAAAUUCGUUUUUUUUUUCAAGGCAGAGCAGUCAAUUGAUUAUAAGUAUUUAUUUCUUUUUUCUUCUUGGAGCCCAGAUUAAAAAGAGUUAUUUUAGAUUUAAAAAUUUCCUGAAAUAGUUGAAAAAUUAUUUUUGAGGAGAAAAUUGUAUCCAAGAAACCCAGAAUGUAAGGAUACUUGAUUUUUAUAUCCAGAUAAUUCUUUCAUGCACUGAAUGGAAGACAGUAUAUCUGUAUAUUAAUUUUUGUUUAGAUUUUGAAUCAUUUAACCCUUAUCCUUUUUUCUUGUAAUAAGACUAUUUAAUGUUUUUCUCUUGUGUUUUCCAUCUUUAUCAAUGCAUUCGUGUUGGUCUUGAUGUAUACUACCUGUUCCUAGUGUUAUUUUUACACGUCAUCUCACAGUAAUAAUAUCAGCAAUUCUUGCUGCAUUGAACAUAUUAAAUACACAUGUAAAAUGAAAAAGUAAGCAGUAGGUAAAAUCUUGUUACUCUGCUUUGCAUUCUGCCUAACUCACUGCAUUUGAAAAUACAUGUCAAAUUCUUUCUGAGGGUAUGUAUGAUUCUUAACUACGUGUCUUACAGCAAAGUUGCCCAUGGGAACAAAGGCUGUAGGGUGUCAUUGAUCUUGUAAUACAACACAUAUUUGAUGGGUGAAUCUUAUUAGCACUCCUUUGAAAAUGUUCCAGUAUGGAGUCAGUUGCUGAUAAAGAGGAAGUUCACAGCUAGGAAUCCGAAGUUAAGAUUUCUCAAUUGCCGCCUGGGCACUCAUGCCUGUAAUCCCAGCACUUGGGAGGCCAAGGUGGGCAGAUCACCUGAGGUCGGGAGUUCAAGACCAGCCUGGCCAACCUGGUGAAACCCCCCCAUCUCUACUAAAAAUACAAAAAUUAGCCAGGUAUGGUGGUGGCUGCCUGUAAUCCCAGCUACUCAAGAGGCUGAGGCGGGAGAAUCACUUGAACCCAGGAGGCGGAGGUUGCAGUGAGCCGAGAUUGUGCCACUGCACUCCAGCCUGGGUGACAGAGCAAGACUCCAUCUCAAAAAUAGAAAAGAUUUCUCAAUUGCCAAAAAGAUUAACAAGUAAAUCAAUUCUGCUCCCCCAGCCAUGAAAAGUGCCCAAAACAGCCCUUUCCCUCCAGAAUAAAAUAAAACUUCCAUUUCUAUUUUUAUGAUUCUCUAAGAUAUCUGAACUCCAUUGCAUUUCAUAGGGUUAUUCAGUUAGCACUUCUGUGGUUUAAAAGACAACAAAUGAAAAUAAGUAAGUUCAGUUUGGGGCAUGAAGAAGUCCCACAUCUGUCUAUAUCUUUUCUUCAUCAUAUUGUCCCUAGGAAUGUAUAGCAAAGCAUUCAGAACUGCUCCUUUGGCUGGGGAAGUUUUCCACCGUCCUUAAUACUAUGAAGUCUUGAUUACUUCUUCCGUGGCUUUAUCCUUGCCUCCCUCCCAAUCCCUGCAUCUUCCAGGAGAAAUAAAAUACCAACUGAACACUGUUACCUUCUCAGCCCUUACCAUUUUCAUCUGCAUAUAGUGUAUAGUACUAAGAGUAGUUUUCCCAGGAGAAAUAAUUGCAAUUUUCAUUUCUUGAUUAUCACUGCUAAUUCGAAGGAGUGCCACAAAUCAUAGCCACUUGAUUUUGAUUUUGGAAUGCAUUUUAGUGUUUUGACACUGGUUUUCCUUUUUUUUAAAUUUUUUUUUCUUUUUUUUUUUUGAGACAGUCUUGCUCUGUCACCCAGGCUGGAGUGCAGUGGCACAAUCUUGGCUCACUGCCGUCUCCGCCUCCCAGGUUCCAGAGAUUCUCCUGCCUCAGCCUCCAGAGUAGCUGGAUUACAGGCAUGCGUCACAGGCUAAUUUUUGUAUUUUUAGUAGAGGCAGGGUUUCACCAUGUUGGCCAGGCUGGUCUGGAACUCCUGACCUCAAGUGAUCUGCCCGCCUCAGCCUCCCAAAGUGCUGGGAUUACAGGCAUGAGCCACUAUGCUUGAUCAGGUUUUCCUCUUUUUUUUUUUUUUUUUUGAGUCAGAAUCUUGCUCUGUCACCCAGGCUGGAGUGCAAUGGUGUGAUCUCGGCUCACUGCAACCUUCACCUCCCGGGUUCAUGCAAUUCUCCUGCCUCAGCCUCCCGAGUGGCUGGGACUACAGGUGCUCACCACCAUGCCCAGCUAAUUUUUUGUAUUUUUAGUAGAGACCGGGUUUCACCGUGUUAGCCAGGAUGGUCUCGAUCUCCUGACCUCGUGAUCCACCCGCCUUGGCCUCCCAAAGUGUUGGGAUUACAGGCAUGAGCCACCGUACCUGGCCCAGGUUUUCCUUUUUUUUUAUGUCUUCUGUACAAUAGAGUUGGCCCUCCAUAUCCACAGGUUCCACAUCCCUGAUUCAAUCAACUCCUGAUAAAAAAUAUUGGAAAAAAUUUUUAUAACAAUAAAAACCAAUAAUACAACAAUAAUUACAAAUAAUACAUUGUAACAAUGAUUUCCAUGGCAUUUAUAAUACAUUGUAUUAGGUAUUAUAAGUAAACGAGAUGAUUUGAAGUAUAUUGGAGGAUGUGCAUAGGUUAUACUAUGCCGUUUUAUAUAAAGGACUUAAGCGUCUGUGGAUUUUGGUAUCUGCAGAGGUCCUGGAACCGGUCUCCCUUGGAUACGGAGGGACAACUGUAGUUCUCUGUCUUUGAAAACAUUAAUCGAUACAAGUGGCCAGUGAAUGUAUAGUAUGGGAGGGAGUAAUCCAGUAUGGGGGACAAGGUUGCCAUAUAUUUGCCAAAAGUAGUUGAAUCUUCUUUCUGUUUUUCCCUCCUGGUGGAAUAAGUUUAUUGUUUGCUAUGAGGAGCCAGAGGCUGUGUUUGUUUAAAGCAAUGGUACCCAAUCUUAAGCAUGUGUAAAGGUCUCCCUGGGUCUGUGAACCAUACCUUGAGAAAUAACUAGAAAAGUAAAAGAAUGGUGAACCACUAUUAAUAAUACUUCCAUUUUGCAUACUAAAUAUGUUGCGUGUACCUGUGUGUGUGUGUUGGGAAUAGUAAUAUGAAGUUUGCUCACAAAACACUCCCACUGUGAUUCACAUUAUUUUAUAGCACAACCAAUAAUGAUUAAACAUAAUUAUUUCCUUUGACUACUUUUCAUUUCAGUGGUAAAACAGCUGAUGAAAGUUAUUUGGGAUGGAAAGAGUAAUACAAGACAUACGCAGAUGGAGUCUCCUGUGCGUAGGUUUAGCACACCCAUGUUAGCUUGUCCACAUUAGGCCUUCUUUUGAAGGUACUGUAUCUAAAGAUAAGGGCAUAAGUGAUCAUUUAAUUCUCAGCCACUUCACUGAUACUACAAGGUGUUACACAGUAAUUAUAGUGGUUUGAUACAGACAUUUGUUUACAAGAAACUGAAUUGGCAUUAUUAACUUAUUUCACACAAAAAAAGUUAGCUUUACCCAUGAACUGUAAUUCAGAUUGAUAAGGUGACCUACCCAUGAAAAAGACACCUGAGACCUGUUUACUUUUUUAAACUAUGAAGUGAAAUCCUCAGUUCAAUAAGUGUCCCAAGGAGAAUUUCCUCUGUUAAAUUUUCCCUGUUAACUUAGUAUAAUUGGUUUUCUUGAAUAGAAGAAUAAUGAUUUCUGUAAGAUAUUUUAAUGUGAAUAUUUUUGCUGUCUUCAUCUUUAAAAAUUAAAUACAGUACUAUAUAUAGAUAUUAAAAUUUUAAAGUGGGACUAGGUGUUUUUAUGUAUACAAUUACAGUUUGUCUCCUCUCUUUGCAAAUUUACUGGCUAUUAUCAGAAUAAAGGUUGGACUCAUUUUGCUUAUCCCAGUCAUUAAAAUGUUGUGAUCUGUUUCUAACAUAUUUAGCAUUUCAUUUUUAAAAUGAGAUGUGCCAUUAUCAUAACAAAGGCAACUAUUAAUGUUCCUAGAAAAAAUGAUGUAAAGGACUUACUCCUAGUCAAUAUUAACACUUAAUCCCACUUUCUUUUUUCCACCAAAUGGCCUCAGUACAUUGCCAAGAGAGUGAAAUUUGGAUUCCUCACAGUACUCAGAACACAAUAUGAUAUUUGUCAGCUAACUUUCCAUCAUGUCUUGGUAAAAUUGCUCAGUUAAAUAUAAUUGGCCAUCUACUUAUUAAAAAACAAUUCAAAUAAUCUGUACAGUUACCAUAAUUUGACAACAAAUUACUUUAAAUUUAGCACCAUCUUAGAAAUCUUCUUAAUAUAAACUACUGAUUGAAAUGUGUUUAUACUUUCUAUCAUAUUUCAAACUGUUUUACUUUCCUUGCAUUAAGACAAUUAAAACACAAACUACAUGUUAGAAUGAAUAAUUUAAAGGACAUGCUGCUGUUUCAGCAUAAAAAAUGGUAAAGUCUUUAUAAAUAGAAUACUUAUGAUAGCCAUUAACGUAUUGAAUUGUUUAAUUAACCUAGUUGUGAUUUUCCGAAUUUAAGACGUUUUCUUACUACAUGUGUUAAAUUGUUACCUAUAAUAUCUUCCUGGAAAAAUAGAAGUAUUUGUAAGGUUUUUAUAAAUGCACAAUUUAUGUAUAAAUAUAAUUGGAAUCUGGGAUGACUCUUAGUAAUCUACUAUUCUUAAUUCAACGAUGGCCACCAGCUACCUGACACAUUUUGUAAAUUUAGCAUCUGUGUAUGUGUGUUCGUGUAUGUGUGUGUGCGUGCAUGUGCACAUUACUGCAUUUAUUCUCAAAUGGAUUUAUAAUUUAGUGUUUUUGUACAAGUACUUGAGCUAUUCAUGUAAUGGGAUAAGUUGCCAUAAAGAUGUACAUAAAUGACCCUUAAUUUGGCACGUUUUCACAUUUAAUUUUUUAAAAUACAGCUUUUCAUAUACAGUUCCUACCCUUUCAUUUCUAGCCUGUACUUCAUUACUUGUUGAAAAAGUCAAGUUUGUAUGAAGCCAGCAUAAACAUCAAAAUAUAACUAAUGUGGACAUCUGUGUAUAUAAUUGAAUUAGACAUUAUGCCUUAUAUAAAAUUCAGGAGGUUCUAAUAUCAAAGGAUCUAUAUGCAUGGAAGAAGAGGCUACAAUGCAUAUAUCAAUGGCUGGCUCUAUGUGGUCAGAUAACUAAACAUGGAAUGCCAAAAAAAAACUAAUGUUAUUAGCAAAUAGAUAUGUUAAUGAAUUAAACUUUGGUAUUUUACUGCAAA